GAAGAGUACCCGGGUUUGGUAGAGUGACUUCUAUUCACUAAAACCAUGUGUCUGAACUGAAGAAGCUUGGGCUCACUUCCACAAAUGUAGCCUUGUCAGAUGAUAUGCAAAUGAUUCACAUCAGUGUUUGAAGUUCAAACCAAGGAAAACUAUCAGAAAAGGCUUCUGCUUUCUUUAAAAAAUAAAACUACUUGAAAAGAAAAAAAUCAAGAAUUAGAAAGAAGAGUAUAACAAUAAAGAAGGAGGGGUCACAGGUGAACGAGAUGUGGUCAACACACACAAAGGAGAACAAAAAGUGGAAAAAUGCUAAUCACUGAAAGAAAACAUUUUCGGUCAGGAAGAAUUGCACAAAGUAUGUCUGAAGCAAAUUUGAUUGACAUGGAAGCUGGAAAACUCUCAAAAAGUUGCAAUAUUACAGAAUGCCAGGACCCAGACUUGCUUCACAAUUGGCCGGAUGCUUUCACCCUUCGUGGUAAUAAUGCUUCCAAAGUUGCAAAUCCAUUCUGGAAUCAACUGUCUGCUUCUAACCCAUUUUUGGAUGACAUAACUCAACUAAGAAAUAACAGGAAGAGAAAUAAUAUUUCCAUCUUAAAGGAAGAUCCUUUUCUUUUCUGUAGAGAAAUAGAAAAUGGAAAUUCUUUUGAUUCCUCCGGUGAUGAACUUGAUGUGCAUCAGUUACUUAGGCAGACUUCCUCAAGAAAUUCUGGAAGAUCUAAAAGUGUUUCAGAACUUCUGGACAUUUUAGACGACACAGCACAUGCCCAUCAGAGUAUACAUAACUCUGACCAGAUCCUACUACACGACUUAGAGUGGCUUAAAAAUGAUCGGGAGGCUUAUAAAAUGGCUUGGUUAAGUCAACGCCAGCUGGCCCGCUCCUGCCUUGAUUUGAAUACAAUUAGUCAGAGCCCUGGAUGGGCCCAGACACAACUUGCGGAGGUCACCAUAGCUUGCAAAGUAAACCAUCAAGGAGGGUCAGUACAAUUACCUGAAUCAGACAUCACUGUUCAUGUGCCCCAAGGUCAUGUGGCUGUGGGAGAAUUCCAAGAGGUGUCUCUAAGGGCUUUCCUUGAUCCGCCACACAUGCUUAACCAUGAUCUUUCGUGCACUGUGAGCCCGUUGUUGGAAAUCAUGUUAGGCAACCUCAAUACAAUGGAAGCCCUUUUGCUGGAGAUGAAAAUUGGGGCUGAAGUAAGAAAGGAUCCUUUCAGCCAAGUCAUGACAGAAAUGGUGUGUUUACACAGCUUGGGUAAAGAAGGCCCUUUUAAAGUUUUAAGCAACUGCUACAUUUAUAAAGACACCAUCCAAGUCAAGCUAAUCGACUUGAGUCAGGUAAUGUAUCUAGUGGUUGCUGCACAAGCUAAAGCUCUUCCGUCACCAGCUGCCACCAUUUGGGAUUAUAUCCACAAAACCACCUCAAUUGGAAUUUAUGGACCCAAAUAUAUCCAUCCCAGUUUUACUGUUGUUUUAACAGUUUGUGGACACAAUUAUAUGCCAGGACAGCUUACAAUUUCUGAUAUUAAGAAGGGUGGAAAAAACAUAUCUCCAGUUGUGUUUCAGCUCUGGGGGAAGCAGUCAUUUUUACUUGACAAGCCACAAGAUUUAAGUAUUUCUAUUUUUUCCUGUGAUCCUGAUUUUGAAGUAAAGACAGAAGGAGAAAGGAAAGAAAUUAAACAAAAGCAGUUGGAAGCAGGUGAAGUAGUUCAUCAACAAUUUUUAUUUUCUUUAGUUGAGCACAGAGAGAUGCACUUGUUUGAUUUUUGUGUUCAAGUGGAGCCUCCCAAUGGUGAACCAGUUGCACAGUUCUCUAUCACUACUCCUGAUCCAACCCCAAACCUAAAAAGACUCUCGAAUCUGCCAGGCUAUUUGCAGAAGAAGGAGGAAAUCAAGUCUGCUCCUUUAUCACCAAAAAUUCUUGUUAAAUAUCCUACAUUUCAAGAUAAAACAUUGAACUUUAGCAACUAUGGGGUAACCCUGAAGGCAGUGCUAAGACAAAGCAAGAUUGAUUACUUCCUUGAAUAUUUCAAAGGGGACACAAUAGCUCUCCUCGGGGAAGGUAAGGUAAAAGCUAUUGGUCAGUCCAAAGUGAAAGAAUGGUAUGUAGGAGUCCUCAGAGGUAAGAUUGGACUUGUACACUGCAAAAAUGUCAAGGUGAUUUCAAAGGAGCAAGUAAUGUUUAUGUCAGAUAGUGUCUUUACAACCAGAAAUCUUCUUGAACAGAUUGUCCUGCCUUUAAAAAAAUUGACUUAUAUCUACUCAGUUGUAUUAACCUUGGUGUCAGAAAAAGUUUAUGAUUGGAAAGUUUUAGCUGAUGUCCUGGGUUACUCACAUCUGUCCCUGGAAGAUUUUGAUCAAAUUCAAGCAGACAAAGAAUCAGAGAAAGUUUCUUAUGUUAUAAAGAAGUUAAAGGAAGAUUGCCACACAGAGAGAAAUACAAGGAAGUUUCUGUAUGAACUUAUUGUGGCUCUUCUGAAAAUGGAUUGCCAAGAGUUAGUCGCACGUCUCAUCCAAGAAGCUGCUGUUCUGACUUCAGCUGUCAAGCUUGGAAAAGGCUGGAGGGAACUAGCUGAAAAGUUAGUACGACUCACAAAGCAACAAAUGGAGGCAUAUGAAAUUCCUCAUCGAGGAAACACUGGAGAUGUUGCUGUUGAGAUGAUGUGGAAACCUGCCUAUGAUUUUCUGUAUACCUGGAGUGCUCACUAUGGAAAUAACUACAGAGAUGUGUUACAAGACCUUCAGUCAGCUUUGGACAGAAUGAAAAACCCUGUGACUAAACACUGGAGAGAAUUAACUGGAGUUUUAAUACUAGUAAAUUCUUUGGAGGUUUUGAGAGUAACUGCAUUCUCCACUUCUGAGGAAGUAUAGAAACAAAGCGUGUGUUUUUGAUGGGAGGGAAAAUGAGGUAAUGGUGUGUGUGUGUGUGUGUCUGUGUGUGUCUGUGUGUGUCUCUGUGUGUCUGUGUGUGUGUGUCUGUGUGUGUGUGUCUGUGUGUGUGUGUGUGUGUGUGUAGGAAAGAAAGAAUCUCAGAAAAGCAUUAUAUUAAUUUUCUUCAUGCUCAAAACCAGUUUUUUUUUCCUGAUGAAAGCACAGCCUAACUGAUAACCAAGAUGGGUUUUAUCCUCAAAUAUGUAUUUUUGUGUAUGUUUCAAAUACAAGUAUUAGGCUGCUUUGUUCUUAGAAAGGAAAGAAAAAAGAAAAGUGCCCUCUCUCUCUUUCAGUGUUAUUUUAAAUUUACUAAGUCAAAGCUGUUUGAAUAAUUACAUCACACAGAUAUCUGGGUAAACUAGAGACUAUCAACAUGAUCAAGGCAGUGUUCCCAGGAGGCAGCUAGAAAGAGGGGAAGCAAGCACACACCCUGUGGCCAGUCACGGCUGCCCGCUUUCCACACCUGACCUCUUCAGUUCAUCAGUGGGGUUCACCAGCAUCACCCCCAUUUUUCAUGGGGAGAAACUCAGAAGUGGAGAGAACGUCUGAGGCUACAUAGCCAGUACAAAGUAGGUUUUCUGCUUGAAAAACCUGUUUCUAUUUCUUUUUAAAAAAUCAUACUGCAUAACAGAAUAGUAAAAACAAAAUGCGUGUUAAGACUUACAGGGAAACAGUUGCCGUUUCAUUUUAAGUGAGACUUGCUACUCUUUUUCAUCGUCUCUUGAAAGACUGACAGAAGGAAAAUAUGACUUAUCAGAAAUCUGUUGUCUGCAUGCAUGGACCUAGUGUUUUCAUCAGCUCCCUUCAGCAUCUUGGGACCUCUCUAAUCCUGCCUAAUUUGGGACUUUUUCUGCAGGAUUGUAAUGUAAAAUAGUUCUUUAGCUCUUGGAGAUUUUUAAUAAUACGAGUUAUUAAAAACCACCACCACCAGAAACUUGAUUAACUUGAUUACCCUGUUGAGUAGAGAGGUCUUAACCACCGAAAACACUGAUAUCUUUAUGUUGGCAUGCUCAUGCAAACACAUGUGUGUGUGUGUGUGUGUGUGUGUGUGUGUGUGUGUACCACAGUGUUUUAUAAAGCACAGCCUAAUUGAUUAUAUAGGACAAAAAUUGUAUAGGACCCUGGGUCAGUAUAAAUGCUAAUGGCUGACAAAGUUCACAAAGAGAUGUAUUUUGCUUACUCCUCUGUUCAAUCCUCUGGUUGCCUGCCAGUGUUUAUGUGUGUAUUUGGACAGACAUUCAUUUAUUGUCAUUCAGUCAAUAGGUAGAGUAUAUGUGUCUAUUUUUUGGCAGGCAUAUAGAUGCUUGAGGCUAAUGGGAAAAAACCAGCAUGAACUCUGACUUUAGUAGUGCUAAGUAAUAGAUAAUUUUAAAAAAUGACACCGUUAAAUAGAAAAUGGCAUGCAUACUAACAGUUGCAAUGGAGAGGCUGUGAUGCUACGAGAUAUAAACGUAGAGAUGCCAUCAUGUGAAACUGGAAGUGGGGGUGGGUCAGGGAAAUUUGUUCUUGGAAAGAAAUAAUGAACCUCAAGGAAGAGUAGGCAUUGUCCUGGUGUGGUGGGGUGUAAGCGGUGAUCCCACAAAGCACUGAAGCUCUUAGAUGGGUGGGAGCUGAAUAGGUGCAGAUAGCAGGGGUGAAGGAGUGAAAGGAUAAAAGAUUCAAGGUUGAGAUGAGGAUGGAGCAAGAAGAAGCCACAUUAGGGCCAUUAAGGCUGCUAGAAUUUAGAAAGAAAACACACAGCCUCAAAGAAAUGUGGGUAAGCCAAAGAAGGAUUUUGUUUUGGGAACCUGAAUAAAAGAUGUCCAUUUGGCUAAAAAGUAAAAGCAGAAUCUUUUUAGGGCUUUUAAUAUACCCACCCUGGGAUAUUUGGUAUGCUGGCAAUGGUAAUUCAAAUUGGCGUUUAAGAAUAAUCUUGGCCGGGCGCGAUGGCUCAUGCCUGAAAUCCCAGCACUUUGGGAGGCCGAGGCGGGCAGAUCACUAGGUCAGGAGAUCGAGACCAUCCUGGCUAACGCGGUGAAACCCCGUCUCUACUAAAAAUACAAAAAAUUAGCCGGGCGUGGUGGCAGGCGCCUGUAGUCCCAGCUACUCAGGAGGCUGAGGCAGGAGAAUGGCGUGAACCCGGGAGGCGGAGCUUGCAGUGAGCCGAGUUCAUGCCACUGCACUCCAGCCUGGGUGACAGGCUGUCUCAAAAAAAAAAAAAGGAAUAAUCUGUACGGCUUUCAGUAUUUAUAUUUGAUUAUAAGGGAACACAGCCUGACCAAAUAAUUAUGUAUACACAUUCAAGGACAGAAUUUAUUUUAAUUAAAAAUAAAUUAUGAGAGAAGGAAAAAAAAGCACAGUUUUUACUUUCAGAACACAGUCCUUUUUUGUGGUGAUUUUGCUUUCUUUAGAACAUUCUUGGAAUCUUAUUAACAUGUCAGCUAACCAGAGAAUUUUGGGAAGGGAUAGUGGGGAUUAAUAACUGGGUUUUUCCAGGCUCCAAGAUCUAAGAAGACAGAGAUCUUGUUAGCUGAUUAGUGUAGUAAGAUUAAAUAAAUAAUUUAAGGUUUACAUUGCAUCAUGUAUUAUGAUUGUGAUUGAGAAUAAUAAGAGUUUAAAAAAAUGAAAAACAAGAUCUCUGUAAUUUGAGGAUGAAACAAUGGUUCUAAUAUUAAUACACACAAAUAUAUUUUAUAAUCUUGUAACAAAUCCUUCCAGGGGAAAUUUUUUUUUUUUUUUUUUUUUUUUUUUUUUGAGCCAGAGUCUGGCUCUGUUGCCCAGACUGGAGUGCGGUGUUUCAAUCUUGACUCACUGCAACCUCCACCUCCUGGGUUCAAAAGAUCCUUCUGCCUCCGCCUCCCAAGUAGCUGGGAUUACAGGCAUGCACCACCUUGUCCGGGUAAUUUUUGUAUUUUUAGUGGAGACAAGGUUUUACCAUUUUGGCCAGACUGGUCUGGAACUCCUGACCUCAGGUCAUCCACCUGCCUCGGCCUCCCAGAGUGCUAGGAUUACAGGCAUGAGCCACUGCUCCCAGCCUUCCAGAGGAAUUUUAAGCCCAUGUCCAAACAUUCUGUUUGUAUAAAUAUAUUCUAAUUUUUAAAUAAAUAGUUUCUACUUUUCUGAACUUUAUAUUUUUUCUUGCUAUAAUGGAUUUUCAUAAUCAGAAAAGAUUAAAUUAGUAAUCAUGAAUUGCCUUCAAUAUUUGGCAGUAAGUCAAUGAAAUAAUAAGGCACUUAUAUACCAUCUUUGACAUCAUUAAAAGUAUCAAAUCCCAUUAAUCUAAAACUUCUUUAAGCAUUUUGAAAGCAGAAAAUGUUUACAUGGUUCUUUCAGUUCCUCAGGCUUUUUGUCUAAUGAUGCGUGACUUAGGAUAAGAUUUGAAUUAAGUGCCCAGCUUGAAACAUAAUAAUUUUUCUGUAUAAGCCACAGAUCCUCUACCUCCUUUGUGUUAAAGCCUUUAUAUGAAACAAUUAAGUAGAAGCAUUCAAUAGUGUGUCAUUAACUGUUCAUACUAAUAAAUGGAUACAGCACAUUUUCAUGGCCUGUAAUGUAGAACAUACUAUAUAAAGUUCUCAGUUUGGGGAUGACUAGGUUUCUGGAAGGAAUAGAAUGCUAAAUCAAUGGAUGGCAUUGGGCUGAGAAACACUGCUGCUACUAAUCAGCCUUGAAUGUGUAAUGUGAACAUGCAAAAGAGAACAUGCAUACACUCAAAUUUGUACAAUGCUAUAACUGGAAGUUGAAGGACUUGAAUUUUUAUAUUGUGCUAUUGUUAUGUUUUCUGUAAUUGUUUAUAUCUAAGGAAUUUUUGAGGUAAUAUAAAAGAAAAAGAGAAUAAUGAACAAUGAUGUCACUGGAGGGUUUUUACAUUAAAUUAGAUCAUUUUUCUUCUUAUUCACAAUAAUAAUCUUAAUCUUUAAGAAUUAAUUAUAAUUUAAUAUUAUAAUUCAUAAUCUUUAAGAAUUAAUAAUUAUAAUUUAAUAUUAUAAUUAAUAAUCUUUAAGAAUUAAUAAUAUAAUUUAAUAUUAUAAUUAAUAAUCUUUAAGAAUUAAUAAUUACAAUUAAUAAUUAAUAAUAAUCUUAAUCUUUAAGAAUUAAUAAUAAUCCUUAAUCGCAAUAAUAAUCGCAAGGAGGAGAAGUAAGUCCCUCCUCCUUCUGUAUGAACUUUUCUCCCACAUGCUGCUGUAUGGUUUAGUGAGAGUGAAGUUCUAAAGAACAUCAAUAUGAUUGGUGGGAUAAUCCAAAGACAUUUUUUCAGAAUCAAAUGGCAUGUCGAAGGUUUGUUUCUUGCAUAUGUAUUUACUGGUCCACAGCACAAAAUAAAGUGACCACAUAUACAUAGGAAAGUUGAAUUUGUACACAUACAGCAUCUGAAAUGUAUCUGAUGUUCAGCAUCAAGAUUUCACUGAACAUUGUAGAAAUGUGUAUCUUUUGCAUGUAUAUUUUACAUUGAUUUUCUAUUUAUGUACAUCUAGAAAGUUUUAACCCUAAUAAAUAGUUUUGUAAUUUUGAAUAAUAGUGUCAGUUUAUAUGUGAGGGAGUAGAGACAGAGAGGUUAGCACUGGAUAAUAAUUAGUAAGGCCAAAGGAGAAAAUUUCAUAGAAAAUAUUGUUGUUGUCAUAAUGAGUACAGCAUGAAAGGCUUCCUCUACAAGACACUAGUCAAAGAGUUGAGAGCUGCGGUUUCUAAUCUUUGUCCAUUACUCCCUUACUCCCUAUGAGACUGUGGACCUGUCACUUGGCCUCUCUGGUCUUCAGUUUUCUCACCAGUAAAACAAGGAACUUGAACCAAAUGACCUCUAGUGUUCCCCUUGGGUUUAAAUGUCUAUAAAUGUUCAAUGACUAGAAUGUAUUGCGUUUUUCUUUAUUCUUUUUGCUUUGAGAAAAGAGAAUGUGAUUUAAGAGUAAUAAUUUGAAUACCAAUUAUCCACAUUAAAAUUGUGUCCUCUAUGUGUAAGGCAUAGCACAUUUAGCACACAUACAUAAGCACACUAAGCACCUUACAAAUAUCCUCAUUUAUUCUUUACAUAAUCUUUUGAAAUUGAUUAUGUAAUACACACUGUUUUUGAACAAUUGGUGACUUCCAGCUGUUUAAAACAAACUACAGUAUGGUGCUUGAGUACUGACUUAGGAGGUCAGCAUUGGUUUCACUAGGAGCUUCUCAAAGCACGCUGCCAAACAUGCUCCAGUCUCAUUGUCAAGGCCUUAGACCAGGCAAUCAUUACGGCAGUGGUUCUUCAACUUCAGCAGCAGCAAAACGAUCUGGCGGGGGCUUGGUGAAACAGACUGCUGGGCUCGACCACCAGAAUUUCUCAUUCAGAGGGUCUGGCCUGAUCACUUGCAUUUCUAAUCACUUCCCAGGUGAUGCAGAUGUUUCUGGUCCAGGGACCCCAGUUUGAGAACCACUGUAUUAAAAUUUCCUUCAUCUCUAUAGAAAUGGAAAGAUUUUUUAUAAGUCCUCUAAUUUGCUUUAAGAUAAAUGAGAUUUCACUUAAUUCUGUUGGAGAAAUUGUUUUAAAAAUUGUGCUAAAGAACCGAAAAUCACUUUAUGUUAAGGCUCUAUUUAUAGCAAGUGAACUUUUCAUGAGUUAAUAAAGGCCUACAAAAAUAAUUUUGACUGUGAAACUAAUUAAAAUCUCUGUGUUUCAUUUAAAGCAUAAACAUAUUUGAAUAAAAAUAGGUUAACAAUAAUUUGGGACAUGUAUUCAGUAUAAUUUUAAGAUAAUUUUACAAAAUAUAUGUAACAUUGCAUUUGUUUCUGUAAAAUAUCUUCGGAAAAAGCCUUGUUUUCCCUAGUGUGUUAUUUGUUGAAUUUCUUGUUAAAUGUAUUUUUUCCCAUUGAAAAAAAUGUUUUUAAUCAAUGUGAUCAAUACAGCUAUCUAUAUGCCCUGCUUUCACUGUAGAAUUAGAAAGUGUUAAUAAGGUGAUCGGAUGUUCUUUCUAAGGAUCAUAUUCCACAUUUAAAGAGAUGGUGACUGAGAAGAGGUGGCAAGCUGAACCAUCUCACUUUGAGAUUGACGUAUCACGUUUUAUCCUCUGCCAUCAUUUCCUUGUUAAUUGUUUUUCUUUGGGUGAUUGGAAGAAUCUAUGGCUUCCUUUUCUCUGUUCUUAAAGAUAUCAAGACUCUGCCCUUUUGUGACUGGAAGUAGAUUUUAAAUGUCCCUAAUGUUUAUAUGCUCACUUAAACUCAAUACAUGGAAUUUACUGGGGCAUUUAACUUGUUCAUGAAAAUAGAGUGAGUCAUUGAAAAAUCAAA